AGGAAGCAGUUCGCUCGCGCCUAGGUUGGCGCGGGCUGGGAGGUGUUCCAGCCCUUUAAGAUGUUGCGCGUGGUGAGCUGGAACAUCAAUGGGAUUCGGAGACCCCUGCAAGGGGUGGCAAAUCAGGAACCCAGCAACUGUGCCGCCGUGGCCGUGGGGCGCAUUUUGGACGAGCUGGAUGCGGAUAUCGUCUGUCUCCAGGAAACCAAAGUGACCAGGGAUGCACUGACAGAGCCCCUGGCUAUCGUUGAGGGUUAUAACUCCUAUUUCAGCUUCAGCCGCAACCGUAGCGGCUAUUCUGGUGUAGCCACCUUCUGUAAGGACAAUGCUACCCCAGUGGCUGCUGAAGAAGGCCUGAGUGGCCUGUUUGCCACCCAGAAUGGGGAUGUUGGUUGCUAUGGAAACAUGGAUGAGUUUACCCAAGAGGAACUCCGGGCUCUGGAUAGUGAGGGCAGGGCCCUCCUCACACAGCAUAAGAUCCGCACAUGGGAAGGUAAGGAGAAGACCUUGACCCUAAUCAACGUGUACUGCCCCCAUGCGGACCCUGGGAGGCCUGAGCGGCUAGUCUUUAAGAUGCGCUUCUAUCGUUUGCUGCAAAUCCGAGCAGAAGCCCUCCUGGCGGCAGGCAGCCAUGUGAUCAUUCUGGGUGACCUGAAUACAGCCCACCGCCCCAUUGACCACUGGGAUGCAGUCAACCUGGAAUGCUUUGAAGAGGACCCAGGGCGCAAGUGGAUGGACAGCUUGCUCAGUAACUUGGGGUGCCAGUCUGCCUCUCAUGUAGGGCCCUUCAUCGAUAGCUACCGCUGCUUCCAACCAAAGCAGGAGGGGGCCUUCACCUGCUGGUCAGCAGUCACUGGCGCCCGCCAUCUCAACUAUGGCUCCCGGCUUGACUAUGUGCUGGGGGACAGGACCCUGGUCAUAGACACCUUUCAGGCCUCUUUCCUGCUGCCUGAGGUGAUGGGCUCUGACCACUGCCCUGUGGGUGCAGUCUUGAGUGUGUCCUCUGUGCCUGCAAAACAGUGCCCACCUCUGUGCACCCGCUUCCUCCCUGAGUUUGCAGGCACCCAGCUCAAGAUCCUUCGCUUCCUAGUUCCUCUCGAACAAAGUCCUGUGUUGGAGCAGUCGACGCUGCAGCACAACAAUCAAACCCGGGUACAGACAUGCCAAAACAAAGCCCAAGUGCGCUCAACCAGGCCUCAGCCCAGUCAGGUUGGCUCUAGCAGAGGCCAGAAAAACCUGAAGAGCUACUUUCAGCCCUCCCCUAGCUGUCCCCAAGCCUCUCCUGACAUAGAGCUGCCUAGCCUACCACUGAUGAGCGCCCUCAUGACCCCGAAGACUCCAGAAGAGAAGGCAGUGGCCAAAGUGGUGAAGGGGCAGGCCAAGACUUCAGAAGCCAAAGAUGAGAAGGAGUUACGGACCUCAUUCUGGAAGUCUGUGCUGGCGGGGCCCUUGCGCACACCCCUCUGUGGGGGCCACAGGGAGCCAUGUGUGAUGCGUACUGUGAAGAAGCCAGGACCCAACUUGGGCCGCCGCUUCUACAUGUGUGCCAGGCCCCGGGGUCCUCCCACUGACCCCUCCUCCCGGUGCAACUUCUUCCUCUGGAGCAGGCCCAGCUGAACCAAUGGAGGCCUGGGGACAUCUGGCAUGGUCACCCCUGCACAUGAUCUGAGGCCAGCUCCCCUUCCCUGAGCUGCCUCCUGCUUCUCCCUCAAAGUCUCCUACCCUUCUCUUCCUCUUUUAAGCCCUCUCUUCCUCGCUUUCCUUCCUACCUAGCUCCUUGUUGGUGAGCUUCUUGUGCCUUAAUCCUGUGACCCAGCCCCUUACACCACUUUCCACCUUCCUGUCCGAAGUACACGGACACUAGCUGCCCCAGGAAGUUGUGUGAUUUUAAAUCACUUCUGUCUUUGCUGGAAAGUGUAUUUGUGCAUAAAUAAAGUCUGUGUAUUUGUUUCAGGGUUGCACUUUGGACAUUGUGGAGGUACUCCAUAAAGUUGAGUCAGAGAAGCUAUCUCAAUACUUGGUUUGCCGGCUGGCUGUAGCCCAAUGAUGUAAUUCCCAGAGAAAGGGGAGGAGGGAGGGGGGAGGAGGGAAUAGUGAGGCGUGAGCAGCAGUGCUCACCAUAAAGGGUUCUCUGCUCAGUUGUAGGAAUUUCCUGUACGGCUAAGGUGAAAUCAGCAAGGAAGGUGGGCUGUGUAGCCUUAAACCAGAGCUUUCCAGCUAGUGCGUCCCACAGCUGCCACAGUGGGUUACAGGGUUGAAAGAAACGGUCCUCAGCCCUCAGAGUUGCCAGGCAGGGCCUGGGACCACACAAGUUUCAGGGACGAUUGCCUCCUUAGCAAGUAGUAUCAUUAGUACCCCUAAGUGUGCCAUGGAAAUGUUUCCUGUAUACUGUGACCUGGAAAGUGGGAGCAUUGCUUUGAACACAGUGCUUGCUCUAGCCAAGCCUCUUCUCACCUUUGAAAAUGGGACUGGUAGACCAGGCACAGUGGUGCACGCCUGUAAUCCCAGCACUUUGGGAGGCUGAGAUGGGUGGAUCACCUGAGGUCAGGAGUUCGCAACCAGCCUAACAUGGUGAGACCCCGUCUCUACUAAAUACAAAAAAAUUAACUGGGCGUGGUGGCGCGUGCCUGUAAUCCAAGCUACUUAGGAGGCUGAGACAGGAGAAUAGCUUGUACCUGGGAGGCGGAGGUUGCAGUGGGCUGAGAUCAUGCAUUGCACUCCAGCCUGGGCAACAAGAGUGAAAUUCAGUCUCCAAAAAAAAAAAAAGAAAAGAAAAAGAAUGGGACUGGUAAAUCCUGUUCUGUGGGAUGCCGUGGGAGGGAGAGAGGAUAAUGGAUUGAGGAAGACAUCCAUAUCCCCUUAUGGAAAAUACCUCUUUGGUUUUGGGGAACCACUCCUUUCUAGGGAAUUUGGUUAGGGCUGACUCAUUUCCUGGCUUCAGGGGCUACCCUGGGCCCAGAUUUCCAGGGCCCGGAUUACCAGUGAAGCGUCAAUCCCUGGAUUUUUAUUGAAACCAUUGGAGAAGAGCCAUCUCAAAUAAAUCUGCCAAGUAUCCUAGCUCUUUGCAACUCACUGUGUAGUUUUUGGGCAUUUCCUUCCUCUUUCUCAUUCUGUUUCCCUGUUGGUAAAAUGGAAUGGUGACCAACAAGUGACCUAUGGUUACCUCAUAGAUCUGCCACUUGUCUGAGGGAGUCAGAAUGCACUUGUCUGUUCCCUGUCCAAUAAAAGGCUUCACAUGC